ACCGGCGGAUUAAGCUCGCUUUCUUCUAGGCGCGUUUCCUGAAGGUGGGAGGGGAGCGUCCGCGAGGCGCUGGGGCGACGGGGCAGGUUUAUCCGGGCUAACUUUGCCGAGUCUGUUUUUGAGGGAAGAGGUUGUGAGGAUCGUAUCUUCCGGGACGCGUUUCACGUGGGAAGGCGCUCCACGCCUGGAACUGUCAGCAGCCGGCGCCUGAAGAGCUCCUGGCGCGGGGCCUCUGGCCUGGCAGCCGCAGGACCCAAUGGAUCAGGCGCUCACGCUGUUCUCACUGCAUGGCUUCAGUGCCUUGCCUGGCACCUCCUAUCCUGUAACUGGCCGACUCGGGGUCCCACCCAGGCUUCUCCAGCGGCCGGGAAGGGGCUCUGCUUCCGGAAGUGUUUAGGAAGGGAGCCAGCGUAAACCAGAGUCCCUUCCUCCAAGCAUCGCUGAAGCCUUUUCUCCCCUGGCAGCCGACUUCCUUUUCUUUGGAAAGGACGUCAGUUUUUUUAGCUUGUUGAAACUGUUCAGAGAUGCGGUCUUGUGGGCAAAUAAAUGCCUGUUUAGCUGAGCUGUUAUUUUCAGCUAAGAAGUUCUUCAAGUUUUCAAGAUCUAGGAGGGGGUGUAGGCUCGAAUUAUAAUGGACCCAGUGUAGCAAAACAUUUAUUCAUUUAAACAAUUGUGCAUGCUCAUUCAGACGCACUACCUGAGUGAGAUGAUGCCGUUCUGGGCUGCUUCAUCUUAAAGAGAGUCACUGUUUCUUCUGGCAACUUCUACCUGCCUUGCCUAUCGAGGUCUCAAUACCAGCUCAGACCAUGUGGACCGCGGAUGAGAUUGCUCAGCUAUGCUAUGAACACUAUGGGAUCAGGCUGCCCAAGAAGGGGAAGCCUGAGCCAAACCAUGAGUGGACAUUAUUGGCAGCGGUGGUGAAGAUACAAUCUCCAGCUGACAAGGCCUGCGACACCCCUGAUAAGCCGGUGCAAGUGACAAAGGAAGUUGUGUCAAUGGGAACAGGAACAAAAUGCAUAGGACAGUCCAAAAUGAGGAAGAACGAGACGGGGUUUCACCAUGCUGGCCAAGCUAGUCUUGAACUCCUGACCUCAGGUGAUCUGCCCACAUUGGCCUCCCAAAGUGCUGGGAUUAAAGGUGUGAGCCACCGCACCUGGAGACAUCCUCAAUGAUAGCCAUGCUGAGGUCAUAGCCAGAAGGAGUUUCCAAAGGUACCUUCUCCACCAACUCCAGUUGGCAGCCACCCUGAAAGAGGAUAGCAUCUUUGUCCCAGGAACUCAAAAAGGAGUGUGGAAACUUAGACGAGACCUCAUUUUUGUGUUUUUCUCCAGCCAUACACCCUGUGGGGAUGCCUCCAUCAUUCCGAUGCUUGAGUUUGAAGAUCAGCCUUGCUGUCCUGUCUUCAGAAAUUGGGCCCACAACUCAUCAGUAGAAGCCAGUAGUAACCUGGAAGCUCCUGGAAAUGAAAGAAAAUGUGAAGACCCUGACAGUCCUGUAACCAAAAAGAUGAGGCUUGAGCCUGGGACUGCAGCCAGGGAGGUCACCAACGGAGCAGCUCACCAUCAGAGUUUUGGCAAGCAGAAAAGUGGCCCAAUCUCACCAGGCAUCCACAGCUGUGAUCUCACUGUAGAGGGACUGGCUACUGUCACCAGAAUAGCCCCUGGUAGUGCCAAAGUGAUAGACGUUUAUAGAACUGGAGCCAAGUGUGUACCUGGAGAAGCUGGAGACUCCGGAAAGCCGGGUGCUGCGUUUCACCAGGUGGGGCUGCUCCGAGUGAAGCCAGGCCGUGGAGACAGAACACGCUCCAUGUCCUGUAGUGACAAGAUGGCCCGAUGGAACGUCCUCGGAUGCCAAGGGGCACUGUUGAUGCACUUGCUGGAAGAGCCCAUCUACCUGUCAGCUGUGGUCAUUGGGAAGUGCCCAUACAGCCAGGAAGCCAUGCAGAGAGCACUGAUUGGAAGGUGUCAGAAUGUGUCUGCUUUACCAAAAGGCUUCGGAGUUCAAGAAUUAAAAAUACUGCAGUCAGAUUUACUAUUUGAACAGAGCCGCAGUGCGGUGCAGGCAAAAAGGGCUGAUAGCCCAGGUCGACUUGUUCCUUGUGGGGCAGCCAUCAGCUGGAGUGCAGUUCCUGAGCAGCCUUUGGAUGUUACUGCCAAUGGCUUUCCACAGGGAACAACAAAGAAAACAAUUGGAAGCCUUCAGGCAAGAUCCCAAAUCAGCAAAGUGGAACUCUUCAGAUCAUUCCAGAAGCUGCUAAGCAGAAUUGCAAGGGACAAGUGGCCACACUCCCUCAGGGUGCAGAAGCUGGAUACCUACCAGGAGUACAAGGAGGCUGCGUCCUCUUACCAGGAAGCCUGGAGCACACUCCGGAAGCAGGUGUUUGGAUCCUGGAUCAGAAACCCACCGGAUUAUCACCAGUUCAAGUGAGAAGGAAAUGUUUGCUCUGGUAGCAGGACCCUUCAUCCUGAACUGCCUUCCUCCACGCAGGACAAGUCUUAGCUUUUUUGGUAGUUAAAUCAGGGAACAUUCUUUCUGAGCUUUGCAUCUCUGUUGUGUAAUACAGAUGGAAUCUGGAACUUAGAGCAAGCUAUACUUGAUUGAAGUAGCUCUCUGCUAAAAUGGCAUCUCACUAAUGACCUCACUAUCUGACUUCCAUUGUGUUUUAUUGCUUCUCUAAAAUAUGAAAUCAGAGUUUGGAACAUGAUGCUUUGAAAGUACUCUGCAGCAGCUCUGUUUUAUGGGUUCCUACAUUGAUUCAGCAAAUAUUUAUUGAGCUGAAAUGAUGUUUGACGCUCUGCAAGUUUUACAGCUUUGCCUAGCAUAGCGAAUAUAUAUUUUGUAUUCCCAGCCUUUCUUUCUUCAGGGAGCCAUUCUUUUCCCAUUCUUCAGUGAUCCUGCUCUGUGCCUCAGACUUGGCUGAAGCUAACCUUACUCCCUGGCUCUAGGAAUAGCCUGUGAGCCAGCCCUGGACUGCCCUGGACUUGUUCUCAGAGGUAUCAGGAAAGGCUUUCUGUUUUGAUCUGGAGCUGUAAGGGUCACAUAAUCAUGGGACUGCCGGUGGCCAUCUUUUCCUACUACCUAGAGAAAGCCAGCAAAGAAUGAAGGCAACAAAGGAAACAGCCAAGAGAAUCAAAGAUCUAGUAACACUGUUUAGAUGUCUCAAUUAUGUGAGACAGAUUCCUGUUGUUAUUUUGAUUAAGCCUGUUUGUGUUGGUUUUCUGACUUACAAUUGAAAGAGUUCUGUCCAAAAAGCCAAAAGGUGGCCAGGCUUGGUGGCUCAGGCCUGUAAUCCCAGCACUUUGGGAAGCCCAGGCAGGCAGAUCACUUGAGGUCAGGAGUUCAAGACCAGCCUGGCCAACCUGGUGAAACCCUGUCUCUACUAAAAAUGCAAAAACUAGCCGGGCAUGGUGGCGCACACCUGUAAUCCUAGCUACUCGGGAGGCUGAGGCAGGAGAAUUGCUUGAACCCAGGAGGCGGAGGUAGUGGUGAGCAAAGAUCGUACCGCUGCACUCCAGCCUGGGUGAUAGAGCAAGACCCUAUCUCAAAAAAAAAAAAAAAAAAAAAAAAAGAAGCCAAAAGGCCCUGCAGCAAAUCAGCAAUAGACCCAGCAGCCAAUCCUGUUUUAACAUCGAAUGUUUAACACUCAACUUCAGACCUUGAAUGAUUGACUGAAAAUGGAAGCUCCCAUGUUGGGGUUACUCAAGGUCCUUAUUGGUUCUUCAGCAUUUUGUGGCUAUAAAUAUUUUUAAAUAACAGUUGUAUUGAGAUAUAAUUCACAGACCAUAAAAUUCACCCAACUAAAGUAUACAUUUUAAAAGUUUUUAGGCCGGGCACGGUGGCUUACGCCUGUAAUUCCAACACUUUGGGAGGCUGAGGCAGGCAGAUCACCUGAGGUCAGGAGUUCGAGACCAGUCUGGCCAACAUGAUGAAACCCCGUCUCUGCUAAAAAUACAAAAAUUAGCCGGGCAUGGUGGUGCACGCCUGUAGUCCCAGCUACUUGGGAGGCUGAGGCAGGAGAAUCACUUGAACCUGGGAGGCGGAGGUUGCAGUGAGUCAAGAUCAUGCCAUUGCACUCCAGCCUGGGUGACAGAGUGAGAUCCUGUCUCAAAAAAAAAAAAAAAAAAUUUUUUUAGUAUAUCCACAGAGUUGUGCAACCAUCAAUUUUAGAACAUUUUCAUCACAAAUUUUGUGCCUGUAAUAGUUUCCUAGAGCUGUUUCUUAACGAAGUACCACAAGCUGGGUGGCUUAAGACAACAGAAAUGUAUUCCUGGCCGGGUGCAGUGGCUCACGCCUGUAAUCCCAACACUUUAGGAGGCCGAGGUGGGCAGAUCACGACGUCAGGAGAUCAAGACCAUCCUGGCCAACAUGGUGAAGCCCCUUUCUACUAAAAAUACAAAAAUUAGCCAGGUGUAUUGGCGCACGCCUAUAGUCCCAACUACUCAGGAGGCUGAGGCAGAAGAAUCUCUCAAACCCAGGAGGUGGAGGUUGCAGUGAGCCAGGAUCGUGCCACUGCACUCUAGCCUGGGUGACAGAGCAAGACUCCAUCUCAAAAAAUAAGAAGAAAAGACUGUAUCCCCUUUCAGUUCUGGAGGCUAGAAGUCCAAACAGGUUGUUGGUGGGGCUUCUGCUUCCUCUAAAAGCUUUAGGGCAGGGGCCCCCAGCCCCAGAGCCACAGACCAUUACUUGUCUGUGGCCUGUCAGGAACAAGGUCACACAGCAGGAGAUAAGUAACAGGUGAGCACUUGAAGUUUCAUCUGUAUUUAUGGCUGCCCCCCAUCGCUCACAUUUCUGCCGUAGCUCCUCCUCCUGUCAUACCAGCAGUGGCAUUAGAUUCUCAUAGGAGCGUGAAUCCUAUUGUGAACUGUGCAUGCAAGGGAUCUAGGUUGCACACUCCUUAUGAGAAUAUAAUGCCUGAUGAUCUGUCAGUGUCUUCCAUAACCCCCAUAUGGGACUGUCUAGUUGCAGGAAAACAAGCUCAGGGCUCCUACUGAUUCUACCUUAUGGUGAGUUGUAUAAUUAUUUCAUCAUGUAUUACGAUGUAAUAAUAAUAGAAAUACAGUGCACAGUAAAUGUAAUUCACUUCAGUCAUCCCGAAACUAUCCCCCUAUCCCCACCCCGGAUCUGUGGAAAAAUUAUCUUCCAUGAAACCAGUCCCUGGUGCCAAAAAGGUUGGGGACUGCUGCUCUAAGGAAGACUUUUUCGUGCCUUGGGGACUGCUGCUCUGAAGAAGACUCUUUCAUGCUUCCUCCUUAGCUUCUGAUGGCUCCUGGCAGUCCUUGGCUUGUGGCUGCAUCACUUCAGUUUCUCCCUCCGUCUUCACAUGGCCUUCUGUGUCUGUGUCUCGCAUGGCCUUCUUCCCUGUGUCUGUGUCUUUCCAUGGCCUACUUAUAAGGACCCCAGUAAUUGGAUUUAGGGCCUGCCCUAAUCCAGUCUGAUUUCAUCUUAACUAACUAGAUCUGCAAAGACUCUAUUUCCAACUAAAGUCACAUUCUGAGGUUUCAGGUAGACAUGAAGUUUUGGGGGACACCACUCAACCCAUUGCAGAACCCAUUAGCAGUCACUUCCCGUUCCUCAACGCCCCCUACCCCAGGGCAAUCAGUAAUCUACUUUCUGUCUGUUUGGAUUUGUCUAUUCUGAACAUUUCAUAUAAAUGGAAUCAUAGAAUAUGUGGUCUUUUGUGACUGGCUUCUUUCACUUAACAUGUUUUCAAGAUUUAUGUUGUAGCAUGAAUCAGUACUUUAUUACUAUUUAUGGAAUAAAAAUCAGUUGUAUGGA